AGUAUCAGAUACAUAGCAGUUUACAUCAUUGGAUUUUAUCCCCUGGUUUAGAUCCAAAGACAUUAUUGGCCAGUCUUAAUGCUUGCUUGUUAGUAAUACUGUUAUGAAAUAAAAGCUUCUGUUGCAGAAGCUUCCUUAAUAGAUAAAACAAAGGCCUUUAACCAGUACGUUACUUAGAGAAUAUUAAUGAAAUAGUUAAAAAAUGAGGGGAAAAUGAUGAAUGCUUUAAAAAUACUGGCCUUUUCACCUUAAUAAUGUGUCAGAACCACUUAUUUUCUACAACACAUGUCUCAAAUUUGCUGGCAUUUCAAAUUCUUAGGAGUUAAUUUUCUAUGUUUGAAUCUUUAAAAAGAAACAUACAAAUGUAGGAUGAAUACAUUCAGAGGGUUUAGUGCAUGCUUUGGCUAGCAAUUCAAUAAAGAUGACUUGGAAGGAUCAAAGCAAAGAUUUCCAUAAAAUUGAAUAUGAGAUAUUUCAGCAACAUCAAUGCUAUACCUCUUCAGGACACUUGUAUGCAUGUCCACAGUACUACCUAGCAUUUACUUAAUGCCACUAGAACAAAAAAGAUAAAUUUUGUUGAGGCUAAUAGAUUUUUAAAAAAUUGUUUUAAAGUCCUUUUAGAGUACCAGGAAAAUCUGACUCAAAGGCAAACAGCAAACAGAAAUGACUUAAUGGAAAUCAGACAAUAAGCCUAAGGAAAAAAAAUAGGGUUGGAACCUAAAAUAAAUUCAAUAUAUAACACCUUUCCAUUUUGUUCCCUUUCCUUUUUGUUUUUCAUGAGAAUCUAUAUGGAAAAGUCAGUUGAUUGCUUAUCAGGCUGAAGCCUGUGUUUGCUCAGACUAGCGAUAAUGAGCAAUAAAAAGGUGGUAAUGGUUAAAGUGAGAGGAGAGGGAAUCAGGGAAAAUGGGUGGGCUCAGUAUAGUUUGCAGGCUCUGAGUUUUGGAAGCCCUGUAAUUCUCCCUUGUGCUGUUAUGUUCAUUGGAGGGGAGUUAAGAUCAGGAUCUGUAAUGAGUGUGGGGGCUUUCCAGGCAGUGGUCUGAUGGCUGCACAAAAGAACUCCCAGUGAUUACCUAGUUACAUCCCUACAGUCAGCUUGGCAAGUAAUCUUAAAGCCUUGCUCCUGAACCAGCAGCAUGAGCAUCACCCAAAAGCUUAUUAGAAAUGUAGAUGCUCAGGCCUGAUACCAGAGUGCCUGGAUAUGAAUCUGCAUUUUAACAAGAUCUUCAGGUGAUUGGCAUACACAUUCAUAUUUGAGAGACACUGACUGAAGGAACACAUGGACACAAGAUGUGAGGACACAUACAGUGUGGGGUGCAGUAGUAGGGUUAUCCUAGGAAAAGAAGGAGCAGACUUUUUAGCUAGUGAGCUAACUCAUUAUAGGCAUGUACAGAUGUUUGUUAGUAGUUUAUCUUUCAAGUUGUAAAGCAAUCAGAGUGUCUCAGGGAAGUCAUUACAUGGACCUUUACAAGCCUGUGACUCUGAGCUUGUGACUCUGUGUCAUAGGAAGCCAGUACUUGCGUAAGAGCCCCAAGGCCAUGUGGGCAAAUGGAGCUGAGAUAAGAAAGCCUGAUAAUAUGAAGAGUGAUCCUAAUCUCAGUGGCCUUUGGGAUUAUGGUUAUCACCAGGUUUUAGAGCUUUGACUCUGGUAAACAAAGAUUCUGCCCUUGGUUUCCAACACAUACUUAUUAUUGAAAUGAUUUAUUAUUUUACUGAAGCAUCUUGUUUCCAAAAUGAACCACCUUAGCCUCCUGAAAUAGCUCUACUGUGUCCCUUGACUUUAAAAGGCAAAUGAGGACUUAUGCCAUUAACCCUGCAGAGUUAUGAUGAAUGGCAGAACUAGAUAGGGCCAUGAAGAUGGCAGGAUAAAAAGAUGCCUGUCUUCGGAGCACCUCUUUUGAAUGGCAUCUCCAAGUCUUCAUCCAAAGACUAGAUUGGUUCUUGUCUCCAUUUUCCCAUUUGGAGCUGCCAUUUUUCCAUAGCAGCCAAGCCCACUAGGUGGUAUUAGAAAUGUCAAAUGCUUGUUCCCUGGUGCCACAAAGAAAUAGCACUUGAACAUUAAUUUUCUCAGUAAGGCAAUUUUUACUUUCUGCAGAAAGGGUGCUCCUCGCAGAUGGAACACGGCCAGAGCACACCUGAACAAAGGAGGGAAGCAAUUUUUUUUUUAAGAUGAAGUUUCGCUCUUGUCCCCCAGGCUGGAGUGCAAUGGCGCAAUCUCGGCUCACUACAACCUCCACCUCCCAGGUUCAAGCAAUUCUCCUGACUCAGCCUCCCAAGUAGCUGGGAUUACAGGUGCCUGCCACCACGCCUGGGUAAUUUUUGUAUUUUUAGUAGAGACGGGAUUUGACCAUGUUGGCCAGGCUUGUCUCGAACUCCUGACCUCAGGUGAUCCGCCCACCUCAGCCUCCCAAAGUGCUGGGAUUACAGGCAUGACCCACGUGCCUGGCCGAGGGAAGCAAUUUUUAUCCCUUACGCAGCUUGUCCCUGCUACUGUGUCCUGUCUCCAUUGGCUGGAGCCAGACCGCACAAUCUAAGCUAAACCCGACUGGCUAUUUCAAAGAGAGCAGGGAUAUGAGCCAGAGUGGUGGGGUGAGUAGUUUGGCAGGAAGGACAGUUAGGAACAGGUAACUAAGGGUGACUUAGGUCAGAGCAGGUGACUAGGAUGAGUCAGGAUGGAGCAGGUGACCAGAGGUGACUCAGGUCAAAGCUGGUGUUGGGGAAGAGUCAGGAUGGAGCAGGUGACCAGGGGAACAGAUGUGAGCUAGUGAUUAGGACUGGAAGGAAAGUUGUUUACUGAAACUAGAAGCAAGAAGGCAAAGAGAACCAGGAAGUUAAACUUUAAAUGGAGAAUCAAAGAAUAAGACAGCUGAACAUACUGACAUAUUGAUUCUUUGAAGAGAAGCUUGGGGUUCACUAUAUUUAACAGUGGUAUGUAAAUAAACUGUUUUCCCCCUGGCAUAGUUGCCUCUAUCAGUGGAGGGUGAGGCUGCAGAUAAAUCCUCUGCCACUUCACCUUUUAUGCCAAAGUCUAAAGGCAAUAAAUACCAAGUUAGAGAAACAUUGACUAGAAAUGGUGAUAUCACAGUAAUCACAAAUCUGUUCUUGUCCUUGCAACUUUUUGACAUAAUGAUCUCAGUUGGCCAGGUACAAUGGCUCAUGCCUGUAAUCCCAGCACUUUGGUAAGCUGAGACGGGAGGAUCACUUGAGCCCAGGAACUUGAGACCAGCCUAGGCAACAUAAUGAGACCCCCAUCUCUAAAAAAAAAAAAUAUUCAAAAAUUUCGCUGGGCAUGGUGGCACAUGCCUGUCAUCUCAGCUACUCGGGAGGCUGAGGUGGGAGGAUUGCUUGAGCCCAGGAUGUCGAGGCUGCAGUGAACCAUGAUCAUGCUAUACUACACUCUAGUCUAGGUGACAGAGUAAGACCAUGUCUCCAAAACAAACAAACAAACAAAAAACCUCAAUCCUGUGUGGCAGAUGGGAGACCUCAGGAGACCUCUGUAAACUGCAUCCAUGCCGUAGACCCCGCAUCCAAGCAGUGCUGCAUCCACCAGCCUUAGGAAAGUGGAUCAGAAAGGAAAUGUCUCAGUGAUCCUAGACACUAACUUUGACAAGGAAAGACCACCCAUAGUGGAAGUGGUUGGAAGGUGAGCCUUCAAAUUCAAGUACCCCAGUUAUUUCAUUAGGGGCCAAAGAGAAUUCUUUUUUCCUAUUUUCUACUAGGGUGCAUUUAAUCUGUAUUAGUAAUGCCACAGAGAACAUUUACUGUCAUAUAAGCAAAGACCUUGCAAAUGUAUUUUAACAGCAGUUCAGAAGACUAAAGAACUUAACAGAGAAGUAGAGAAGAGAGAGCCUGCAAAGUCUACUGUAAAAGUAAAACGUGCUAGUUUUGGCAUCAAUUUAACCACAUUGGAGACUUGGUCAGGAGCACUGAGGCUUGACCACAUUAUCCAAACACAUCUGCUUGCCUUAUCAUAUUGUCCCAUUUACUUUUCUUUUUCUUCUGCCAGCACAAACUUGUGUCAGCAUGUGGAAGUGGUAUUUCUGCUACCUAAUCUGUGUUAAAACAGCCCUGAAGGGUCAUGCAACUAGUCGGAUUGUAAACCUUUGGAGAAGAUUAAACAGUCAUCAUGUAUUAAUCAGUCUUGACCACGUUGUGAAUUAAAAGGUGAAAUUCUUGGCCUUAUUCUAAAAGAUGACAGGUCUAGAUGUUAGAGAUAAGCAUUGUUUUUAUAUUAGUCAGUAUUUCUAUGUAGCCAGUUAUGUUUCCAGAGUAGUGAGAAUUAUUCUAAGAAGAAAAAAGUAUUUUCAGUAUAAACUAAACAAGAGAAAAAUGGAAGUUUAAUACACAUCUGCAGUGAACAUGAACAUAGGAAAACGUGAAAACGUGAGCAUAGUGAAGUUUGAAGUGGGAGAGAACCUUUUCUGAACUGGGUUGCUUUGCUCACAGGCCAGGUAGGAGAGAGCAGGGGAGGAGGUUUUACUGGACCCAAGCGCCUUGUAAGAAUUUUCCAAAAACAUUAAGUAAAAUUUAGUUAGUUGUGAAGUAGAAAGUUAGCACUUCUAUGUCUUCAAGGAAUCCGGUUAUAGUCAUAACACAGAAAAACCAAUCAUCCCUCCCAUAGUAGUUGAAAGAUAAAAUUGACAUCUUCUUGAAAGAGAAAAGCUACUAUUUUAUGAGCUUAGAAGAAAAAAAAUUCUUCAACUUUAUGAUAUGCUAUUUGAGCUCUGUGAGUAUUCAAAUAUAUGUACUUACAGAAUCUCAGUGUUGCAAAUGGAAAAUAAUGAUGCUGUCUUCAAAAUGACCCCCCAAAAAAAAUCAGAGAAAGGGUUCAAGUGCUGCUGAAGUAGCAGCCUCUGGAAUUAAAGGAAGUGAUUGCCAGGCCGGGGAAGUGAAGCAAACAGAAUAGUCCUGAACAGAAGACAGCCGCUGCCCUCACUUCCUUAUGCACUGUGCUGUUCAGCCCAGGCACUUACUGUUUCUCUAAGUGUGAUGCAGAAACUAGCUUGACCAGGGUUUAAGAUAAUGGUAACCCUCACAGGUUUUGCGGUGCUCCACUUUCUGCAAAUGAUCAAACUUCACUGUCAAAGAAAUCCAGAUUCUCUUAGAAUCCUAGCAGAGUGUGAUAUUUGACUUUUUUGGGUUUCUAAAUUUUGUUUUCAUUUCUUUGAUGCAGUAGAUGUAUGGCCCAUGGUGCUUUUAAAUUCUCUGCAGUCUAAAGUAAAUGACAGGGAAGAAAACAAAUAUUCUCUGGACCCCAUUAAUGAAAGACAAAGGGACAGCGAGGGUCCUUUAGAAAAGGGUAUUAAAAAUGAUAUAUGCCUGUAAAAGGUCGGGGAGGGAUCUCAUGGGAAGAAAUAAAGUGCAAUAGAGUAAUGAAGAAGAAAAACGGUAAUGCUGAAUGUCCUUUAAAAGAUACUUUAUUUUUCAAAGAAGUGUCCAGAAUUCUAACUUAUAUAAACACUAGAAUAUUGAUCAGUUAUGGUAGCAGACUUUGGUGCACAAUUCUCAGACUGACACAUGAUUUGGUUAGCAGGUAACAGCUGUAAAGGAUGUAAGAAAUAAUUAUCUGAGAUUCCCUAUGCAAAGUCUUAAAAAAAAUUCUACACCAAUUUCUGUAUCUCAAAUGAAGAGGGCAUACAAAGAGACAAAAUGCCUGAUGGUUCCCCAGGAUACUGUCCCAGCAGCAGGGACAGAGUCCUUAGAUAACAUGGAGAAGAAAAUGAAUGGGCACUACCAAUGUAUUUGCCAAGAUAUGACAUGUGCUUCUGCACAUGAGACUUCAUAACUGGAUAAAUAAAGCAUCUUAAAGAACUUACGUUCUUUUUCUUCCCUAGAUACCCAUUCAUGUGUAAAAUGUUACCGAGUUCACGCUAUUUUUUGUUUGUUUGUUUGUUUGUUUGUUUUGAGAUGGAGUCCCAUUCUGUCGCCCAGGCUGGAGUGCAGUGGCGUGAUCUCAGCUCACUGCAACCUCCACCUCCCAGGUUCAAAUGAUUCUCCUGCCUCAGCCUCCUGAGUAGCUGGGAUUACAGGUGCACGCCACCACGCCCAGCUAAUUUUUGUAUCUUUAGUAGAGAUGGGGUUGCGCCAUGUUGGCCAGGCUGGUCUCGAUCUCCUGACCUCAGGUGAUCAGCUCACCUCAGCUUCCCAAAGUGCUGGGAUUACAGGUGUGAGCCACUGCACCCGGCCUGCUCUAACUAUUAAUUAGUCUUUGAACUUGUAAUGACAAUAAUGCGAACUUAGUACUGACAGAAUGAACUUGUGUGAGUGACCUCUUAGUAUAGGAACAUGUACAGUGUUUAACACUUUAUUAUGUCAUGUUAGUAUGUGGUUGCUUCCUUUCAGAACAUUGCUUUCAAGUGUUAUUGAAUGUUAGUAAACAUGAAAAAAAUAAAUAAGAAUUUUGGUGAUUCUUACCCCUCUUACCUCUAGGGUUUCUGAAAACUGACACAGUAGGUUUAGAUAAAGAUGUGUGGUGUUAAUUUGAAUCUGCCAUACUUUGAAUUUAGAAUGCACUGGACACGUUGAUAUCACCAAUUAGCAUUCUGUGUAGCCAGGCUAGCAUGUGAUUCAACUGUUGUGUUUACCCUCCACCCCAACACCCAUCACCGCUGAUCUACAUGAAUGUUAUCAAGCAUUUGCAGCCUGAAAAAGACAUGAUGUAGAUUUGACUCCUGUAGUUUCUUCCAAAUAGUAUCAAGUGCGGCAGAACAAUAUCCCCCGUAAGUCACUUACAUUGUCAUCUUAAUAUUAUCAUGAUUGUGAAUUCUGUUGUCUUGAGAUGGAUCGAGAACUUUGACAUCAGUUCAGUAUUGCUAAUGGAAUAUAUUAUUUACACAAGACUUUUUCCUGUCUGCAUUCAGCCAUGUAGAAAUAUACUACCAUCUUAAGUGCCAGAAGAUGCUGAUCCGAAGUAGAAGUUGUUGGCAGGUAUUGGUGCCAGUUAGAUGAGAAUAAACUGCCAAGGAAGACACUGGAGUGAAAAAAGAUAGUUUGGGCCAAGUUUUUUUCCCUCUCUCUCUCACUCUUGAAAUAGGUAUCUAACAUGCAUAUACACAACAUCAGUCUAUAGGAAAUAUGAGGGAUGCUUGAUUACAAGCAAACAGGGACAUGUGGGGCCAAACUCUGCCCCCAGCCCCUAUCUUGCCAUAUAUGUUUCUAGUAGAGAUGAAAGUGACAUGUGGGAAUGAUGGGGGGAUUCAUGUCUUCUAGACUUCACAGUAUGAAAGGGACCAGGCCUUCCCAGGAGGAAUGGCCAGAAACUGAAGCUAUAGCCAGAAAUCAAGGGAUCUUUUGUGAACACCUAAAGCAGGAGUUUAUCCAGGGAUAGAGAUCUCCAAAUGGUGGAAGCAACAUACAGGCAGGGGACAGAAAACAGCCUCCAUGCUGUGCAAGCAUAAGUUUGUACUGAUGGCAGAGCCUAGUUUGGUUUGCAUUUACCGUAAUUUUUACUCAUCUACUUUUAAAGUGGUAUUUGAAGUGAUUGUGAAUCAAAGGCAUGAUAAUGCAUACUUUUCCCAAUUUAAAAUAUACUGUUUUAUAUAUGUAACUACAUGCCUUGAAAAUAAUGAGUAUUUGAAUCCUAUCACAUUUUUUGGAAAAAAUAUCAGACUGAGCAUAUAAAGAUCAAUCUUUUACAUAACCAACCAGUGGAAGAAAAGGGGUUUUGUAAAACGUAUGCAGUUUAGCGCAAGAAAAUAAGAAAAAAAGAACUUGCAAUGAAAGGAAAACGAACAGAAAAUAGUGAGAUGAGAAAAUUCCCAAGUACAUUUACUCAAUAAACUAAAACUUUACUUUAACCAGACAAAAGCAAAAUGCAUUCUAUAUCUCCUGUGAGUUUAAGAUACACUGGGAAGAAAAAUUGGCAUGACUCAUGACUUAAAUAAUUAAAAUUUUAUAUAAAAACCAAGAGGUUAACAAAAAGUUCAGGCCAGAAGUAAAAUAAUAAUUAAAUGUAAAGUAUCUGAACUGCAAAAAUCCUGAAAAAUAAUUUCCACCACUGAUGGAAAUGGUUUUAACCAUUCUAGUGGUGAAGAUCAAGUUGUUGAAGGAAAUCCAUCAGUUAUUAUGUAUAUUUUAGUGUGAUUUGAAGGGGAUUACAGGAGUAAAAUUAAAGAAAGUACACACACACACACACACACACACACACGCACAGAAUUAUUAAAAUGUAUUGCACUGAAGGACAAGUUAACCAUACUAGAAUCUAGGGAGCCAUUUCUCAGGAGUACAACCUAAGAAGCAGGAUGGAAGCUCUGCACACUGCCCAGUACAGCUGCAGAGGCAAGAGGAUUCUUACAAGUCAUGACUAUCAAUGAUUUGUUUUGUUCUCAGAUUGCAAAACAAGGAAAAUGCUUUCAUAGCACGUCAGAUUAUGUGCCUACUCAAUAGUCUAUAGAUCUUUAGCAACCUUAGAAUUAGGAAUAUGUGACAUAUACUUCAGAAGGAAAGCUACAAAAACAAAAAUUACAGAAUCAAACCAGGAUUGCCUCCAACUUUAGGAAGCAGGACCACCGUAUAAAGCUUGCCCAGAUCGUCACAGCUAAAAGCCUGUUGAGAAAAGUUGUCUAGGGCCAAAGAAAUAAAUAUUGUCUAGGCUUGAACUCUAGCACUGCCAUUUUGGGGACAUUGGGUUGUGGUAGAUAAGAAGAAUAGGGUGUAGAUGUCUGAAAUUAUCUUCUAUAUAAUGGAGAAAAAUUUGCUUGAUUGCAAACACACAAUUGAAAAUAUUUUCUUAGUUGCUAUGAAUUACUUCCAGUGAAAAAUAUGCCAACUCCAAUAAUUUAUUUACAAAAAAAGGAUAUUUGUAACAAACAAGCAAAGGCAAAGAAGGAAAAGAAAACUCUAGAAAAUACAUAGGAAACAGCAUGGUAAUAGGGUGCCCCUGUUGUGGAAUAGGCCAGGGGUAUUGCAGGGUGAAAGGUUCAAGAUGAUGAUGGUGAUGGUGACAAGGUGAUGGUCAAGCAGGACUUUAGUUUUGUCUAAAAUGUUUAUUUUAUUUAUUUAUUUUAUCAUUAGAAGGUUGCCAUGUAUUAUUUGUAUAUUUAAUAUAAGUACACAAAGAGUAGCUACUAAGAAGUACAUUCUAACAAAUGUAUAAUGAGUUUAAGGACAGAUAAAAAAAUUUCAAACUUUUGUUGAAGGCAAAAACACAUCUAAUUGAAAUUCUGUUCCUCUGAGCAGAACGAUCUUCAAGACAUAUGUAAAAUAAUAGGGCUAGAAGUACCUUGGAAAACAUGGACCUGAAAAUAAUUCAUUAUCCCAGCACACUGAGGUGGCUCCACGUGAGUCUGUCAUCUCAGGACAGAAAGUGGUGUUGUGUCCUGGCAGUCCAAGUUGAGGACACCCACUGCUCAUAAAAAAAAUAUGAAAUUAAAUAUUCAGCAAUAAAUUGUUUUGAGGAAGACAAAAUGCUUUUAAAGGAUCAACAAAUACCUAUCAUUGCAAAAAAAACUCAAACCAAUGAGCCCAUACAGAUGGAUCAGAGGCAUAAUAUUCAUGUGUAAAGUAUUUGGUCCAAGUUUUUUUUGUGUGUUUUGUUUUGUUUUGUUUUGUUUUGCUUUGUUUUUGAGAUGGAGUCUUGCUCUGUAGCCAGGCUGGAGUGCAGUGGCGUGAUCUCAGCUUACUGCAACCUCCGCCUCCCGGGUUCAAGCGAUUCCCCUGCCUCAGCCUCCCAAGUAGCUGAGAUUACAGGCAUGCGCCACCACACCCAGCUAAUUUUUUGUAUUUUAGUAGAGACGAGGUUUCACCAUGUUGGCCAAGAUGGUCUUGAUCUCCUGACCUCAUGAUCCGCCCGCCUCGGCCUCCCAAAGUGCUGGGAUUAUAGGCAUGAGACACCGCACCUGGCCUGUUCCAAGUUUUUAGGAGCAGAUGAAGCUGUUAAACUUUUUGUUUGUGCCACCUGUCUAUAUUAAUUCUCUGUAUUUUCCCCAUAUGCUUACUUGCAUACUUAUAUGGUUAUUCUCUGUGUAUUUCCUGUUUCUUUUCUCUCUUUUUUUCUAAAUGUAUUGAAAUUUCUGAGAAGAUGAAAAUACCACCUUUAUGGCUACUCCUAAUGGCAAUAAGCGUAGUCACCAACAUUUAUUUAAUGUUGGCUCUUUGUUCAAUUAAUCUUUGUGGCAACUGUAAAGGCACAAGUUACUUUAUCUCCAUUUGGGGGUUAAAUCUGUUGAAACUCUGAAGAAGAAAGGAAUUUGUCUCUAGGUCAUGCAACUGGAAACCCUGGACUUGAACCCCUAGCACUGAUAUAUCCUAGGGGUUCUAGUUCAGAUUAGACUGAUGCUAGAACCCCUGACCUGGUCUCCACAGACCCCUCAACACUGCUUCACGUGCAGAGCAGGAAGCACCAGGACAUCCUUCCUAAGUGGUGUUAAGAACUUGAUCUGAUGAAGUAUCCAUGUGUCUUUGAGUAAGUCAUUUAACUUCUCUGGAAGAACAGCUUCUUUACAAAGUAAGGUCACAUGCCUCUUAGUUCACACAUCCUUCCCAGUUCUAACUUUUCUGUGAUUGUAUUUUCUUUUACUGCCCUAUUCUCAAGAAAUGUAUUUAUUAUGAACACAUGCUGCAGUUUCCCUGUUGGUGGGUCUCUAUGUGUGCAUGCAUGUGUGCAUGUGUGUGUAACUGUUGCGAACACUUACCUUCUAACUGCUGUUGGAGCUGCUUCCAGCUAAGUAGGUGUUCCAAAUACCAGGCUGCUCUUAUUAUGGACUUGGUUUAAAGGAACGCCUAUUCUUUUUUUCACACAUGCUAAUACAAUGUCCAUCUUUCCUCUCCUAAUAGCCCAUGAGUCUUGAACUUGGAGUCAGCAAAGUGCUGCCUUUGUACAGCACAAAAGAACACCAGUUUUGCUUUUUUUUUUUUUUUUUUUUUUUUUUUUAAGAAAUCACACGGGGACUGAAUAAAAAGCUUUUCGACCAUUCAGAGGCUGCUUGCAUUGUGCAGCUGUUCCUUGACUGCUGAGAACAUCUCCCGCGGACAAUGCAGUACCUGAAGAGAACACGGCACAUGGAGCUAUUCAAGAGUUGCAGGACCUGGGACUGGUGCCAGUGUCCUCUGUGGAAGAUCGGGGGCCUUUCUUCUUGGUCAGACCCUGAUAAGCAUAUUGCAGUUUGUGGCAGUUGUUGUUUUUUGUUGUUUGCCUGCCAGCAUUAGUUUCACAAUUUUAUUGCAAUGAUGCAUUCCCAACAUGCUGGCACUUAGGGGAUUUUGUUCUUUCCUCUUUUGGUCCCACCUCCGUGAAAUGUACAGUGAGACUUUGAUUGGUCAUAGUCCACUUACAGUUCGCAAUGCGUUACUGUGUGGACUGAGUUCCCAUGACUCGGGCUCCCCAGGACAAUGUCUCUUUCUUCACCAAGCUGAUGGGUGAAGUAGAGAAAUAAAGUCUCCCCGCUGAACUACUAUGAGGUCAGAAGCCUUGCUGCUAUAUUUCACACUGCUACACUUUGCUGGGGCUGGUUUCCCAGAAGAUUCUGAGCCAAUCAGUAUUUCGCAUGGCAACUAUACAAAACAGUAUCCGGUGUUUGUGGGCCACAAGCCAGGACGGAACACCACACAGAGGCACAGGCUGGACAUCCAGAUGAUUAUGAUCAUGAACGGAACCCUCUACAUUGCUGCUAGGGACCAUAUUUAUACUGUUGAUAUAGACACAUCACACACGGAAGAAAUUUAUUGUAGCAAAAAACUGACAUGGAAAUCUAGACAGGCCGAUGUAGACACAUGCAGAAUGAAGGGAAAACAUAAGGAUGAGUGCCACAACUUUAUUAAAGUUCUUCUAAAGAAAAACGAUGAUGCAUUGUUUGUCUGUGGAACUAAUGCCUUCAACCCUUCCUGCAGAAACUAUAAGAUGGAUACAUUGGAACCAUUCGGGGAUGAAUUCAGCGGAAUGGCCAGAUGCCCAUAUGAUGCCAAACAUGCCAACGUUGCACUGUUUGCAGAUGGAAAACUAUACUCAGCCACAGUGACUGACUUCCUUGCCAUUGACGCAGUCAUUUACCGGAGUCUUGGAGAAAGCCCUACCCUGCGGACCGUCAAGCACGAUUCAAAAUGGUUGAAAGAACCAUACUUUGUUCAAGCCGUGGAUUACGGAGAUUAUAUCUACUUCUUCUUCAGGGAAAUAGCAGUGGAGUAUAACACCAUGGGAAAGGUAGUUUUCCCAAGAGUGGCUCAGGUUUGUAAGAAUGAUAUGGGAGGAUCUCAAAGAGUCCUGGAGAAACAGUGGACGUCGUUCCUGAAGGCGCGCUUGAACUGCUCAGUUCCUGGAGACUCUCAUUUUUAUUUCAACAUUCUCCAGGCAGUUACAGAUGUGAUUCGUAUCAACGGGCGUGAUGUUGUCCUGGCAACGUUUUCUACACCUUAUAACAGCAUCCCUGGGUCUGCAGUCUGUGCCUAUGACAUGCUUGACAUUGCCAGUGUUUUUACUGGGAGAUUCAAGGAACAGAAGUCUCCUGAUUCCACCUGGACACCAGUUCCUGAUGAACGAGUUCCUAAGCCCAGGCCAGGUUGCUGUGCUGGCUCAUCCUCCUUAGAAAGAUAUGCAACCUCCAAUGAGUUCCCUGAUGAUACCCUGAACUUCAUCAAGACGCACCCGCUCAUGGAUGAGGCAGUGCCCUCCAUCUUCAACAGGCCAUGGUUCCUGAGAACAAUGGUCAGAUACCGCCUUACCAAAAUUGCAGUGGACACAGCUGCUGGGCCAUAUCAGAAUCACACUGUGGUUUUUCUGGGAUCAGAGAAGGGAAUCAUCUUGAAGUUUUUGGCCAGAAUAGGAAAUAGUGGUUUUCUAAAUGACAGCCUUUUCCUGGAGGAGAUGAGUGUUUACAACUCUGAAAAAUGCAGCUAUGAUGGAGUCGAAGACAAAAGGAUCAUGGGCAUGCAGCUGGACAGAGCAAGCAGCUCUCUGUAUGUUGCGUUCUCUACCUGUGUGAUAAAGGUUCCCCUUGGCCGGUGUGAACGACAUGGGAAGUGUAAAAAAACCUGUAUUGCCUCCAGAGACCCAUAUUGUGGAUGGAUAAAGGAAGGUGGUGCCUGCAGCCAUUUAUCACCCAACAGCAGACUGACUUUUGAGCAGGACAUAGAGCGUGGCAAUACAGAUGGUCUGGGGGACUGUCACAAUUCCUUUGUGGCACUGAAUGAGGCCAAUAUUUUAUUUAUCAUGUGCAUGGUGAUCAUACUUCAAGGCUGGAGCUUUUGGAGUUGUUGGCAUUCCAGUUCCCUCUUGCCCAGCACAACCACAUCAGAUUCGACGGCUCAAGAGGGGUAUGAGUCUAGGGGAGGAAUGCUGGACUGGAAGCAUCUGCUUGACUCACCUGACAGCACAGACCCUUUGGGGGCAGUGUCUUCCCAUAAUCACCAAGACAAGAAGGGAGUGAUUCGGGAAAGUUACCUCAAAGGCCACGACCAGCUGGUUCCCGUCACCCUCUUGGCCAUUGCAGUCAUCCUGGCUUUCGUCAUGGGGGCCGUCUUCUCGGGCAUCACCGUCUACUGCGUCUGUGAUCAUCGGCGCAAAGACGUGGCUGUGGUGCAGCGCAAGGAGAAGGAGCUCACCCACUCGCGCCGGGGCUCCAUGAGCAGCGUCACCAAGCUCAGCGGCCUCUUUGGGGACACUCAAUCCAAAGACCCAAAGCCGGAGGCCAUCCUCACGCCACUCAUGCACAACGGCAAGCUCGCCACUCCCGGCAACACGGCCAAGAUGCUCAUUAAAGCAGACCAGCACCACCUGGACCUGACGGCCCUCCCCACCCCAGAGUCAACCCCAACGCUGCAGCAGAAGCGGAAGCCCAGCCGCGGCAGCCGCGAGUGGGAGAGGAACCAGAACCUCAUCAAUGCCUGCACAAAGGACAUGCCCCCCAUGGGCUCCCCUGUGAUUCCCACGGACCUGCCCCUGCGGGCCUCCCCCAGCCACAUCCCCAGCGUGGUGGUCCUGCCCAUCACGCAGCAGGGCUACCAGCAUGAGUACGUGGACCAGCCCAAAAUGAGCGAGGUGGCCCAGAUGGCGCUGGAGGACCAGGCCGCCACACUGGAGUAUAAGACCAUCAAGGAACAUCUCAGCAGCAAGAGUCCCAACCAUGGGGUGAACCUUGUGGAGAACCUGGACAGCCUGCCCCCCAAAGUUCCACAGCGGGAGGCCUCCCUGGGUCCCCCGGGAGCCUCCCUGUCUCAGACCGGUCUAAGCAAGCGGCUGGAAAUGCACCACUCCUCUUCCUACGGGGUUGACUAUAAGAGGAGCUACCCCACGAACUCGCUCACGAGAAGCCACCAGGCCACCACUCUCAAAAGAAACAACACUAACUCCUCCAAUUCCUCUCACCUCUCCAGAAACCAGAGCUUUGGCAGGGGAGACAACCCGCCGCCCGCCCCGCAGAGGGUGGACUCCAUCCAGGUGCACAGCUCCCAGCCAUCUGGCCAGGCCGUGACUGUCUCGAGGCAGCCCAGCCUCAACGCCUACAACUCACUGACAAGGUCGGGGCUGAAGCGUACGCCCUCGCUAAAGCCGGACGUACCCCCCAAACCAUCCUUUGCUCCCCUUUCCACAUCCAUGAAGCCCAAUGAUGCGUGUACAUAAUCCCAGGGGGAGGGGGUCAGGUGUCGAACCAGCAGGCAAGGCGAGGUGCCCGCUCAGCUCAGCAAGGUUCUCAACUGCCUCGAGUACCCACCAGACCAAGAAGGCCUGCGGCAGAGCCGAGGACGCUGGGUCCUCCUCUCUGGGACACAGGGGUACUCACGAAAACUGGGCCGCGUGGUUUGGUGAAGGUUUGCAACGGCGGGGACUCACCUUCAUUCUCUUCCUUCACUUUCCCCCACACCCUACAACAGGUCGGACCCACAAAAGACUUCAGUUAUCAUCACAAACAUGAGCCAAAAGCACAUACCUACCCCAUCCCCCACCCCCACACACACACACACACACACAUGCACACAACACAUACACACACACGCACAGAGGUGAACAGAAACUGAAACAUUUUGUCCACAACUUCACGGGACGUGGCCAGACUGGGUUUGCGUUCCAACCUGCAAAACACAAAUACAUUUUUUAAAAUCAAGAAAAUUUAAAAAGACAAAAAAAAAAGAAUUCAUUGAUAAUUCUAACUCAGACUUUAACAAUGGCAGAAGUUUACUAUGCGCAAAUACUGUGAAAUGCCCGCCAGUGUUACAGCUUUCUGUUGCAGCAGAUAAAUGCCAUGUUGGGCAACUAUGUCAUAGAUUUCUGCUCCUCCUCUCUUUUAAUGAAAUAACGUGACCGUUAACGCAAGUAACUCUUUAUUUAUUGUUCACCCUUUUUUUCCUUAAGGAAAGGACUCUUCCAAAUAUCAUCCUAUGAACAGCUCUUCAGAAAGCCCAUUGAAAGUUAAACUAUUUAACGUGAAAUCCAUUAACUGGAAUAAUUGAGUUUCUUUAUUUUUACAAUAAAUUCACUGAGUAAAUAAGUUGGAGCUGGAAUUCUGAGCUUUGUGUUUGGACUGUCUGGUCUGUAGCUAAAGGAAAAAGUUAGGAGGGGAAUAUUUAUUUAAAUCUAUCAGUUCAUUGCCUGGUCAGGUCUCUGGCCUAUAAACAUGCAAAAAAACUAAUUCAUGUUAAAGUCCUUCCAGAUCCUAAUUUCUAAAGCAAUCAGGAGAGAAAGCUUUUAGAAUGGCACAUCAUAUCUCAUUGAUGCCAACAUGGUUUUGUCCAUGGUUCUGACUUUCUGUGAAGGCACCAGCUUGCAAUAUGCCAUCCCAUUUCACCUUGCAUGUGAGACAGCAAACAAAAUCCACAAAUGGUGUGAACUAAUAUGCUGGCUGCUACCUUGCAUAAAUUAAUGAUUUGAUCACACGGGUUCUUCGUGGGGUUACAUCUGUGAAUAGCCUGUUUUCCACAUGUAAAUUUGUGCCUUACACCUUGAGUUGUGUACACUUGUAAACUCUUUAUGAUCAACUGUUCCCCCUUUUGAAAUAAGUGCAGAUAUUUAUUUAACCCUCCCUUCCCCACCCUCUGCCCCACUUCCAGCCCUCUGAAAGAUUGGAGUCAAGCAGAUGGAAGAAUGCAGUGGUGAUAGUUGUCAUGCGACAGCCUGAGAACGCUGGGCAGCACCACACCCUCCAAUUCACACUGCCUUCUAGUUGUGCCAACUGGAACCACCCUUUGGCUGUGCUGCGAAGCAUGGACCCCAGUGUUGUUGUGGGUGUGUCAAAUCCCCUUUCAUCCUCAAGAGCUCCCUGCUUCCCUUAGAUUAUUUCAAUACGGUGAUAUCCUUAUUUGCUAGCAGAAAAGGGACUAACGUCCCAUUCCUCUUUUCUGCUGCGUCCACUGGCUAGAGAGCAGGCGGUGCGCGGUUGGGCAGACACCUGGGAGGAGUCUCCAAGCCAUGUGCACAGCACACACGUGCAGUGCACACAAAGAAAUGACAUGGAAAUAGAUGCAGGCAGGCUGGUCCCUGCUGUGAUUAACGAGUAACUCCAAGUACAAGGCCGACCACAAUGGAUGCUGCAAAAACGUUGACUGGGGCAAAGGAUUUUUUAUUUUAUUUUUUAUUUUGUUAAUUAUGUUUUUAGGGGAUGGGAGGUGGUGUGUGUUUUUCUCCUCUUGGUUUUCAUUUGCUCAAGCACACAAAAGGGACUUUUGUUUACUCUAUCAUGAACAAAGGAACUGUCCACAUACUGUAAACCAUGAGCAGUGUUGUUGUUGUUUUUUUAAACAGUAUAUUUGGUGGUCUCUUUGUCUGCUUUUAUUUCCAGUUCGAUCUUCUGGGUUUAGUUUUGUCUUUAAAAAGAAUUCAAAAAAAGACUGACAAUGACAGUUUUGAGUUGGAUAGUGAAAAAGUGGAGCCUCCAUAAUCAGUGUGGUUGCCUUCAGACCUGAGUACUUAGCUGAGGGUGGGUGAGAGCCCUUUGUUCCAAAAGUCCAUUAGUUUUGCUGUUGUUUAGGAGUAGGUGGUUGUUGUUGUUUUUACUUUUUUUUUUUUUGGCUUUUGUAAUGGAAUCCAUGUUCACAUCCUGUGAACUCUGUCUCCUGAAACCCUGAAGUAUUUCCUAGAACCUGAAAUAUUGUUUUCUUCCUUGAAUUUUCUCUAGAAAUGCAGAAAUUAGGAAGGUGAUGGGUCUGUAUCCCCCUGCCCCCUUCUUUCCCAUGCUUGACUCCCGAGAGUACUGGCAGUGCAGCACCCAUCAUUGACGUAAGCGGCUGUCUUGUCCAGUGUUUGUAGGCAUCACUGCCUCAGCUGUUAAGGAGACCUGUGUCAAAACUUACAUCCACAUUCCUACACCCCCACAACCCAUCACUUCUGGUGUUAACCCUAAAAUACCCACAUGUAUUGAGCUGGUCUUCUGCAUUUAAGUAUUUCUCCCCAGUUUUUUUCCCCACUGUGUGUGGGGGGAGGGUCCAUAAACCCGAGUGUGCCUUUGCUUUCCACCCUUGCUAGACACUGGUAGAUGCAACAAACUCAGAUUUAUAUUUGUUGUAAAGUUGUAAAAAUAUUGUGAUGUCACCAAUUUUCCUUCCAUCUCCACAUCCCCUAACAUCUGAUUCACGACUUAAUGUAUGUUGUAAGAAAAGAAAAAAGAAAAGAAAAAAAGGGAAAAAAGAAAAGCAAGGAAAAGGCUCUUUAUUACUUAAAAGUAAUAAAACCUGACUGUUCUAUAUUA